ACAGCGCACCGGGCCGGGGGAGCGGCCGCGCUGGGCCGGGCGGGCGGGUGGCGGGGGUGCGCUCGGGGACCCGGGCCGCGUGGGCGCCGGGAUGGAGGGCGCCAAGGGGCGGGGAGCGGGCGUGCGUGUGUGUGCGAGUGCGAAUGCGAGGGAGGCCGGCCUUGAGUGAAACCGGAGCUACAAAGAAGGGGAGAGUCCGGGAGCGGGAGGGCGCGAGGGAGGAGCGGCGGCGCCGGGGCAGCUCCGACGCCCUCCCGCGGGGAAGGAGCCCCCGCGGUGCCGCCGAGGCCCCGACGCGGGGCCGCCCCUCGGCUCGCCGCCCCGCGCCCGCGCCCGCUGGGAAUGAUGAAGAAGAACAAUUCCGCCAAGCGGGGACCUCAGGAUGGAAACCAGCAGCCUGCACCGCCCGAGAAGGUCGGCUGGGUCCGGAAAUUCUGCGGGAAAGGGAUUUUCAGGGAGAUUUGGAAAAACCGCUAUGUGGUGCUGAAAGGGGACCAGCUCUACAUCUCUGAGAAGGAGGUAAAAGAUGAGAAAAAUAUUCAAGAGGUAUUUGACCUGAGUGACUAUGAGAAGUGUGAAGAGCUCCGGAAGUCCAAGAGCAGGAGCAAGAAAAAUCAUAGCAAGUUUACUCUUGCCCACUCCAAACAGCCCGGUAACACGGCACCCAACCUGAUCUUCCUGGCAGUGAGUCCAGAAGAGAAGGAAUCGUGGAUCAAUGCCCUCAACUCUGCCAUCACCCGAGCCAAGAACCGUAUCUUGGAUGAGGUCACCGUUGAGGAGGACAGCUAUCUUGCCCAUCCCACUCGAGACAGGGCAAAAAUCCAGCACUCCCGCCGCCCCCCAACAAGGGGACACCUAAUGGCUGUGGCUUCCACCUCUACCUCGGAUGGGAUGCUGACCUUGGACUUGAUCCAAGAGGAAGACCCUUCCCCUGAGGAACCAACCUCUUGUGCUGAGAGCUUUCGGGUUGACCUGGACAAGUCUGUGGCCCAGCUGGCAGGGAGCCGGCGGAGAGCGGACUCAGACCGCAUCCAGCCCUCCGCAGACCGGGCAAGCAGUCUCUCCCGACCUUGGGAAAAAACAGACAAAGGGGCCACCUACACCCCCCAGGCACCCAAGAAGUUGACGCCCACAGAGAAAGGCCGCUGCGCCUCCCUGGAGGAGAUCCUAUCUCAGCGGGAUGCUGCCUCUGCCCGCACCCUCCAGCUGCGGGCUGAGGAACCCCCAACCCCUGCCCUCCCCAACCCGGGGCAGCUGUCCCGGAUCCAGGACCUGGUAGCAAGGAAACUGGAGGAGACUCAGGAGCUUCUGGCAGAGGUUCAGGGACUGGGAGAUGGGAAGCGAAAGGCCAAGGACCCCCCUCGGUCUCCGCCGGAUUCUGAGUCAGAGCAGCUGCUGCUGGAGACGGAACGGCUGCUGGGAGAGGCAUCAUCGAAUUGGAGCCAGGCAAAGAGGGUGCUGCAGGAGGUCAGGGAGCUGAGAGACCUGUACAGACAGAUGGACCUGCAGACCCCGGACUCCCACCUCAGACAGACCACCCCGCACAGUCAGUACCGGAAGAGCCUGAUGUGAGGGCAGGGUGGGGUCUGGAACUUGUCGGGUUGGACAGACUCUUAUCUCCGUGUUGCUGGAUAAAGCUUUUUUAUUUACCUCAAUCAAAAAAAGAAAACAAAAAUGAACUCAUUGCUCUUGCUGAUGCCUGACCCCACUACAACCCUUAUUGCCCCACCUACUUUCCAUAUGCCCCUCGUAUGCCCCUCAGGUUUGAGGAAGUGACCCCGCAGCAGUAGCAGGAAGUUUUUACCCAGCCAGAGAGAGAGAAGGCACGGUAAAGACACAGUCUGACCACUCCACACACCGCCCGCCCCCAAGACGGCACAGGGAGUCCACUGCUGCUCCCAAGGAUACAGUGGGCUUCUAAGCUUAGAGCGGGAGGGGGAUGAGGAUGUUUUCUGUUAUGUCCCACCCCAGGCCUUCAGUUUGAGGGUGAAGUUUCAGCUGCCCAACUCUAGUUGUAGGGAUGUGGAGGCCAGUGUCACCUGUCCGUGCACAUGGAAGUGAAAUUUAUCCCAGCCCUGAGGAGGAUUUGUGGAAUUAAAAUCUCCCCAGCCAGA